UUCCCACUCAGGACCGUGCUCCCUGGGAGGACCCUCGUAAUUUAUGCUCUGCCCUAGAGCCGCUUUCCUGGUGGGAUCCUUUCAUGGCGUCUUCCCAGGACCUCCUGCCAGCUCCCAUUGGGAGUUUUGGGUCCCCUGCACCCCAGUAGGUGCAUACUUCUGCCCUCCCCAGCCCCAGCUCACACCCCCCAACAUCCCCAAGCUGGUGAGUGAGGUGGAGGAGCUGAACAUGUCCAUCACAGCGCUGCGGGAGAAGCUUCUAGAAGGGGAGCAGUCCCUUUGCAACCUCGAGGACAUCCACAUGAGCCUGGAGAAGGACGUUACCGCCAUGACCAACAGUCUCUUCAUCGACCGCCAGAAGUGCAUGGCCCAUCGUACUUGCUACCCCACCAUCCUGCAGCUGGCUGGCUACCAGUGAGCAGCGGCACGGUGCUUCCCCCCAAUCCCCCAAAUAAACAGUGCAUUAGCUUUC